GGCCCUCCCCCCACCAUGGCGCGGAGCGAGGCAGCGGCGGCGGGGCCGGGCCCGGGGCCCCCCCGGGCUGGGUGAGCGCGGCCUGCAGCGGCCCGGGAGCGGCGGGCGGGGGCGCGGGUGUGUGCGCGGGUGUGAGCGUGCGAGCGUGCGAGUGUGUGUCCGUGGCGCUGCGGCGGGCCCGGCGUGCGCCCGCGCGGCCCUAUGUGUGCCCGGUGCCGGCGUGUGCGGCGCCCUGCCCGUGUGGCCAUCGGGUGUGCGCGGGGUGUCGAGCCCGGCCGGCGUGUCCGGCUGUGCACGCGUGUCCCCCCGAGCGGCCGCCCCUCCGGCUGUGUGUCUGGGCGCUGUCGCGCGCCCAUCGGAGGGGCUGUGUGCAGGUGCUGGCCCAGGCCCUGACUCCCUGAAGAGAGAUGAAGAAACCGAGAAUCAGAGAGGUUCAGAUACUUGCUGGAGGUCACACAGCUAGUCUCACCUCCCACCCCUCCUGCCUUCCCACUGCACCAUGGCUCCAGGACCCUUCUCCUCGGCCCUCCUCUCGCCGCCGCCCGCUGCCCUGCCCUUUCUGCUGCUGCUCUGGGCGGGGGCAUCUCGUGGCCAGCCCUGCCCCGGCCGCUGCAUCUGCCAGAACGUGGCGCCCACACUGACAAUGCUGUGCGCCAAGACCGGCUUGCUCUUUGUGCCGCCCGCCAUCGACCGGCGCGUGGUGGAGCUGCGGCUCACCGACAACUUCAUCGCCGCCGUGCGCCGCCGAGACUUCGCCAACAUGACCAGCCUGGUGCACCUCACUCUCUCCCGGAACACCAUCGGCCAGGUGGCAGCUGGCGCCUUCGCCGACCUGCGUGCCCUCCGGGCCCUGCACCUGGACAGCAACCGCCUGGCGGAGGUGCGCGGCGACCAGCUCCGCGGCCUGGGCAACCUCCGCCACCUGAUCCUUGGAAACAACCAGAUCCGCCGGGUGGAGUCGGCGGCCUUUGACGCCUUCCUGUCCACCGUGGAGGACCUGGAUCUGUCCUACAACAACCUGGAGGCCCUGCCGUGGGAGGCGGUGGGCCAGAUGGUGAACCUAAACACCCUCACGCUGGACCACAACCUCAUCGACCACAUCGCGGAGGGGACCUUCGUGCAGCUUCACAAGCUGGUCCGUCUGGACAUGACCUCCAACCGCCUGCAUAAACUCCCGCCCGACGGGCUCUUCCUGAGGUCGCAGGGCACCGGGCCCAAGCCGCCCACCCCGCUGACCGUCAGCUUCGGCGGCAACCCCCUGCACUGCAACUGCGAGCUGCUCUGGCUGCGGCGGCUGACCCGCGAGGACGACUUAGAGACCUGCGCCACGCCCGAACACCUCACCGACCGCUACUUCUGGUCCAUCCCCGAGGAGGAGUUCCUGUGUGAGCCCCCGCUGAUCACACGGCAGGCGGGGGGCCGGGCCCUGGUGGUGGAAGGCCAGGCGGUGAGCCUGCGCUGCCGAGCGGUGGGUGACCCCGAGCCGGUGGUGCACUGGGUGGCACCUGAUGGGCGGCUGCUGGGGAACUCCAGCCGGACCCGGGUCCGGGGGGACGGGACGCUGGAUGUGACCAUCACCACCUUGAGGGACAGUGGCACCUUCACUUGUAUCGCCUCCAAUGCUGCUGGGGAAGCGACGGCGCCCGUGGAGGUGUGCGUGGUACCUCUGCCUCUGAUGGCACCCCCGCCGGCUGCCCCGCCGCCUCUCACCGAGCCCGGCUCCUCUGACAUCGCCACGCCGGGCAGACCAGGUGCCAACGAUUCUGCGGCUGAGCGUCGGCUCGUGGCAGCCGAGCUCACCUCGAACUCCGUGCUCAUCCGCUGGCCAGCCCAGAGGCCUGUGCCCGGAAUACGCAUGUACCAGGUUCAGUACAACAGUUCCGUUGAUGACUCCCUCGUCUACAGGAUGAUCCCGUCCACCAGUCAGACCUUCCUGGUGAAUGACCUGGCGGCGGGCCGUGCCUACGACUUGUGCGUGCUGGCGGUCUACGACGACGGGGCCACAGCGCUGCCGGCAACGCGAGUGGUGGGCUGUGUACAGUUCACCACCGCUGGGGAUCCGGCGCCCUGCCGCCCGCUGAGGGCCCAUUUCUUGGGCGGCACCAUGAUCAUCGCCAUCGGGGGCGUCAUCGUCGCCUCGGUCCUCGUCUUCAUCGUUCUGCUCAUGAUCCGCUAUAAGGUGUAUGGCGACGGGGACAGCCGCCGCGUCAAGGGCUCCAGGUCGCUCCCGCGGGUCAGCCACGUGUGCUCGCAGACCAACGGCGCAGGCACAGGCGCGGCACAGGCCCCGGCCCUGCCGGCCCAGGACCACUACGAGGCGCUGCGCGAGGUGGAGUCCCAGGCUGCCCCCGCCGUCGCCGUCGAGGCCAAGGCCAUGGAGGCCGAGACGGCAUCCGCGGAGCCGGAGGUGGUCCUUGGACGUUCUCUGGGCGGCUCGGCCACCUCGCUGUGCCUGCUGCCAUCCGAGGAAACUUCCGGGGAGGAGUCUCGGGCCGCGGUGGGCCCUCGAAGGAGCCGAUCCGGCGCCCUGGAGCCACCAACCUCGGCGCCCCCUACUCUAGCUCUAGUUCCUGGGGGAGCCGCGGCCCGGCCGAGGCCGCAGCAGCGCUAUUCGUUCGACGGGGACUACGGGGCACUAUUCCAGAGCCACAGUUACCCGCGCCGCGCCCGGCGGACAAAGCGCCACCGGUCCACGCCGCACCUGGACGGGGCUGGAGGGGGCGCGGCCGGGGAGGAUGGAGACCUGGGGCUGGGCUCCGCCAGGGCGUGCCUGGCUUUCACCAGCACCGAGUGGAUGCUGGAGAGUACCGUGUGAGCGGCGGGCGGGCGCCGGGACGCCUGGGUGCCGCAGACCAAACGCCCAGCCGCACGGACGCUGGGGCGGGACUGGGAGAAAGCGCAGCGCCAAGACAUUGGACCAGAGUGGAGACGCGCCCUUGUCCCCGGGAGGGGGCGGGGCAGCCUCGGGCUGCGGCUCGAGGCCACGCCCCCGUGCCCAGGGCGGGGUUCGGGGACCGGCUGCCGGCCUCCCUUCCCCUAUGGACUCCUCGACCCCCCUCCUACCCCUCCCCUCGCGCGCUCGCGGACCUCGCUGGAGCCGGUGCCUUACACAGCGAAGCGCGGGGAGGGGCAGGGCCCCCUGACACUGCAGCACUGAGACACGAGCCCCCUCCCCCAGCCCGUCACCCGGGGCCGGGGCGAGGGGCCCAUUUCUUGUAUCUGGCUGGACUAGAUCCUAUUCUGUCCCGCGGCGGCCUCCAAAGCCUCCCACCCCACCCCACGCACAUUCCUGGUCCGGUCGGGUCUGGCUUGGGGUCCCCCUUUCUCUGUUUCCCUCGUUUGUCUCUAUCCCGCCCUCUUGUCGUCUCUCUGUAGUGCCUGUCUUUCCCUAUUUGCCUCUCCUUUCUCUCUGUCCUGUCGUCUCUUGUCCCUCGGCCCUCCCUGGUUUUGUCUAGUCUCCCUGUCUCUCCUGAUUUCUUCUCUUUACUCAUUCUCCCGGGCAGGUCCCACUGGAAGGACCAGACUCUCCCAAAUAAAUCCCCACACGAACAAAAUCCAAAACCAAAUCCCCCUCCCUACCGGAGCCGGGACCCUCCGCCGCAGCAGAAUUAAACUUUUUUCUGUGUCUGAGGCCCUGCUGACCUGUGUGUGUGUCUGUAUGUGUGUCCGCGUGUAGUGUGUGUGUGUGUGUGUGUGUGUGUGUGUGUGUGUGUGUGUUGGGGGAGGGUGACCUAGAUUGCAGCAUAAGGACUCUAAGUGAGACUGAAGGAAGAUGGGAAGAUGACUAACUGGGGCCGGAGGAGACUGGCAGACAGGCUUUUAUCCUCUGAGAGACUUAGAGGUGGGGAAUAAUCACAAAAAUAAAAUGAUCAUAAUAGCUAA